AGUGACCGUAAAGCUGUUCGCUCGGUGCGACGCAAGUCUCAGCUCAGCGCGCUUAUCCUGGGUCCACCGGCGCUACCGCCCCCCGACGUGAGAGAGCGAAGUUCUUGGGCCGCGCUCCCUCCCUACCUGGGUGCCCUCCCCCUCCGGGAGCCUGGGUCCCCGGGGCGGUCGCGGCGGCUGCAUCCUCAGGCCAGGCCGCGGGGGGAGGGGGCGGCACGGGCCUCCGAAAGCGGGGCCAUGGAGCCCAGAGAGUCGGGGAAGGUAGGACUGGAAGGCCCGGGGGCCGCCCGCUCCCUCCCGAGGAUCCCCGAGCCGGGCUCGGGCGAGGCGGGGCGGCUCGGGCGGAGGCCCCGCAGAUGAGCCAGGCUUGCAGGGAAGGACUCGCCGGCCCGCCCUCUCUUCCCGCACUUCGGCGCCCGACCCCGGGAGGGUGGCGGAGAGGAGCGGACGCUUCCGUUCGGUGUCCGCGCAUCCUCCCCGAGCUGCCGAGCGUCCGCUGGGUCGAUGCUGGGUUGGGUGACCCCCGAGUGGAGCGAUGCGAAGGUGCUUCCUGUUUUCCCCACCACCUUCGGCGUUUUGAAGAGGCCCUGCUAAGGCUUGGAGUCUGGAUCGGACGCCAGUGGGAGCUGCAGGGUGGGACGCUUGAGGGCUUGACCCUGCCUAGAUCCUCCUUACCAAGAAAGGGCUGAAAAGAGAGGGCAUCUGGCAUGCUUUUUGCCACUUCUGUUUCUAGGUUAUGUACUUCAUGGAAUAUCUGGGCAUUGCUUAGAAACCUGUGUCAUAAAUUGGCUUUGGGCAAGAGGCUUUGAGUUGGAAGAAAAGGUGGAAAGAAAGUGCUUGGGGGCGGAGUUCAGGGAUUUGACGGGAUUGCCAGCGCUUCCAGGCCGUGUCAUCCAAGACCAGUGUGGUUGUGGGCACAUUAGCUUGGAGACAGUGGCAGCCUCUUGGGACUAACAUCUUUCUGGAUGUUGUUUGCUGCCAGUUCUUGAGUAUUGUUUCUUAUUUGGCACAGAGGAGAAUUCUCUCAACAAACGUUUUCGACUGUUUAUUGAGUCCCUUAAAAAACUGUCCAUUUAAUAAACAUUUGUGAUCUGUGAUUUGCAUUGAACGAGAUGCUGGAAGUAUGAGGAUAAAUAGGAAAUGAUCACCUUUCUCAAGGAGCUCUCCUGCAGUUUUCACUUCAAUAACUUGGACACGCCUGAAAGGGUUGUCCCACACGAAAAGAGAGAAAAGGAUAAUGAGGUUCUUUUGAUGCUGUAGUUUUUCCUGGGAAGACUAGGAAGGACUCUGAAUUUCAAAAGAGGUGAUUUCUCGCAUGAGCAUCUCUUCCAUCCUCCCUCCCUCCACAAGCUACAGUGAUGCAUGUAGCAGACACGGCACCUACAGAGUACGUGGUCCAAGCCAAUAAAGCUCAACAAAACCCAAGCAAAGAUGGAGCUUAUGGCCCUUACCCUUUGGAAAUAUCCCCAGAUUGGUUUAGAUUGAACCUGAAUUUGAAUAAAGAGAAGCAAAAUGUAGGGGGAAGAAGGAUUAUAAAAUAUUGGGAUUGAUAUUGGUAUCAGUGAUUUGAAGUUGAUUUCCAAGCUAUUCUGUUCAGUCAGAGGCUUUCUUAGCCUUUAACGGGAGAAGAGAAAUACGGUCAUGCGCUGUAUAACAAGGUUUCCAUCAACACCGCUCUCACGUACAAUCCCCUGAGACUACAGUGGGGCUGAGAAAUUCCUAUCACCUGGUGACAUCUUCAUGAUCCUGACCCUGUGUAGGCUUAGGCUAAUGUGUGUGUUUGUGUCUUAGGUUUUAAGAAAGCUUAAAAAGUAAAAAAAAAAAAAAAAAAAAAAAAAAAAAAAAUUUAAAAAUACAAAACCUCAUAGAAUUAGAAUAUAAAGAAAAAUACUUUUUGUUGAUGGAAUGGUUUGCUGGAAAAUAAAAAUACAAAAAUAUUUAAAGAAAAAUAUUGUACAGGUGUACAAUGUGUGUUAAGCUAAGUGUUAUUACAAAAGAGUCAAAAGUUUAAAAAAUUAAGUUUAUAAAGUAAAACAGUUACAAUAAGCUAGGGUUAAUUUAUUAUUGAAGAAAGAAAAAUUUUUGAUAAAUUCGGCGUAGCCUUAGUGUGCAGUGUUUAUAAAGUCUACAGAAGUGUUCAGUCAUGUCCUAGGCCUUCACAUUCUCUCACCACUCACUCACUCACUCACUCACUCACCCAGAGCAACUUCCAGUCCUGCAAGCUCCAUUCAUGGUAAGUGCCCAAUACAGAUGGACCUUUUUUUUUUUUUUGUCUUUUCUACCAUAUUCUUACUGUACCUUUUCUAUGUUUAGAUACGCAAAUACUUACCAUGUGUUACAGUGGCCUACAGUUUUCAGUACAGUAACAUACUGUGUAGGAUUGUAGCCUAGGGGGCAAAAGGCUAUAUACCAUAUAGCCUAGAUAUGUAGUAGGCUGUACCAUGUAGUUUUGUAUAAGUACACUCUGUGAUGUUCCACAAUGACAGAACUGCCUAAGGACACAUUUCCUAGAACUUAUCCCUGUUGUUAAGCAACACAUGACUGUACAAACAUUUUGGGAGGUAGAGGAGAAACCUGAUUCCGUGUCCUGUCCAACCACUAAGUGAAACCUCAGAGACUGGAAAUUUCACCCUUGAUUAUAAUCUUGAUUUUAGGGUAUCUCAGAAAGGUGCUCACCCUUCCCAAAGAUAGUUGUUUUCUAAUAUGGGAAAUGAGAACUUCAUACAAGAAUGAAAUAAAGUAAUUACAAAACCAACUGUCAGUGUAAGAUGUGUUGCAAAUGAGUGACAAGGAAUAGCGGUGCUGUUCUACAACUCCACUCCGAACAGCAUUCUUAUGGCUCAGAACUGGGAGACUACCUCGUGAGAUAGUGGUUUGGUCUAUUACUAGACUCUUCCUUGGGUGCUGUUUUGUGGUCUUUAUUAACUGACAGCCAUCUUGGGCCAUUGGAUUGAUAUCCCACAUUGAAUGUAGGACAUCUUGCCUGUCAUUGACAGAAUAAUGGAUAAGGGUCAGACUUUUCCCCAUCAUGUUCUAUCCCAUGAUCCUGUUUUAUUUUCUUCCUAACCCUUAUCACUAAAUAAAAUUCUCAUGUUCAUUUAUUUAUUUACGUAUUUGUUGACUUGACUCUUACAUCCCCAGCUAGAACAGUGGAGCAGUUCCUGGCAUUUAAUAGGGUCUCAGGAAGGAAUGCUCAUAAAAUAGCAUCACUACAGGAGCCCUUUUGCUGCAAGGUGUGGGUGCUCUGAAGAACACUGCAGCCCGCCACCUCAUGUGCCUCCUAGGAGACUGUGCUGUUGGUGCCCCGAAAGAGAAGUCUAUAUGUGUACUUGUUGCUGUAUGUAUUUGUUGCCUCAACGUUUCUGUUUCUUGGCCCUCUCUAUCUUUCCUGUACAAGUGACUGAUACUCCUUUCUCAUUUUUUUCUGAACAUGGUUCUAUUAUUGCACUUAUAUCUUAGUUGUCUGCCACCUCCUGAUAGAUUUUAAUCUCAUAUCUUUGAAUUACCAUGCAUCAAGCACAUAGAAACACUUAAGUAAUAAAUGUGUGUUGAAUGAAAAAAUGAAUUAAAUGCCUAUAAAAUACUUUCCAUAUAGCAUGGUUGUGGGGGGAAGGGUGGUGUUGAUGAAGGAAGUUAUAAAAUCAAGCAGCAUAGAUUUCCUUAACACUGGACUCCAGGGGGGAUAUAAAGCCUUCCUUGCUCAGGAGAAGGAUAAAUGCUUGGGCCAGGUGGUUAGGAAAUCCUUCCUGAAAGAGAACGUGAAUCGCGACUUUAUGGGUGGGUAGAUUCUAAGUUGGUGGGAGGAAGUGUGCAGUCAGGAUCUAAAGACUGGGAAUGUAGAGAGAGGAAAGGUGCGAGAUAGGCUGGGUGAUUAAAAUGAUAUGAAUCUGGCUGGAGGAGACAUUCCAAGCGAGGCAAUGCACAGAGCUAAAGUUAGAAAGUGGGUUAGAUUCAGACUGAGGGGACUUUGGUGCUAGACUGAGAAGUCAGACAGCUUUACCUUGUAGAGAGUGACUGGGAACCGCUAAAAUAGAACAUCGAGAGAGAUUCUUUGCAUUACACAUAGGUGAGGAGCUCCUCUUAUUCACGCAGAUUUGUGUUUUCUUUACAUUGCAGUCACCUGGAAUCAGAAGGCUCUUGCUAUAAUAUUGCUUAAGAGAGAUACCAGGUGUUAGUGUUAUCACUCUUGUUAGGAAGACACUAUUAUCCAAAUGGACAGUCCUAGCCAUGUUCCUCCUCAGGUGGAGCUAACGUGAUGGGCUCCUUGGCCCUUAUGCUCACCUGUGCAUGCCCGGGAAGGAUGGGCAUGAAGAGGGAUCCUGGCUGUCCUGAAUCACAAGUGUUUUAACCUGCCCCAAUCUGGACAGGCUGCCCUCCCGUCCUGGGAUACAGCAGUCAUCCUGAAUCUGCCUUCAGCCUAAUCUUGGGGUUGUCUUCAAUGCUUCCCCACGUUGGCUGUCCCUAGGUUGUAUCUCAUGGUGACUCCUGUUUGACCACUUUCUUUGAGUGGAGCUUGUCUUCCAAUCGGUUUUUGGAAAUAUUUCAUUUUGCUUUGGAAGCCACUCGAGCAAACAGUUAUUUAAAUGUACACAUUUGGCAGUACAAUUCCAUUUUUGUUUUUAAAACUGUUCAUACAUAUUCAUAGACUAAAGACUGGGAGGUUAUAUACCAAAUGUUAACAGAUUCUCAGGAAAGAAGGGUAAUGAAAAGUAAUUAUUUUUCAAUAAAGGGAAUGUAGGUGAUCUUAAUACAUUUUUUUCUGCUUAUUUCUAUUGUCCAAAUUUUCUGCAGUCAACAUGAGAAAAAUCUAUUAUAAUAGUGACCGGUAAGAAUGAUUGAUAUCAUUUUCCUCAAGAAAUGUCUACUGUUGAGGUUAAAAUCGAUAUUCCACCUAUUUUAAAUGGCAUGCUGUUAUUUCCCAAUGUUAUUUUUCUUUGGAGUGAGAAGUUUGUUUUUUGUUGAUAAUUUGAUUUAUUUCUUUUUAAAAUUUCUUUAACUAGGUAAUGUUUUCAUGGCACAAAACUUAAAAUGAUAAACAUUUCUACUUCUUUUUCUGUUGAUUUCUUUUAUAACACUUUGUUGCGUGGCUGUGGUACCUUAAACCUCUUUGAUGGUGUAGCUUGAUGAUAGUUUUUUUUAAGUUUUUUUCUCCAUGCCUUCCCUCCAUUUUCUUAGCAACCUGCCCCCCAAACCCCAACACCUCCCAUCUAUUUUGGUCUCUAUAGUCCCUGUUAGAUCCUUUCCCCGAGUGUCUGGUAGUCCAGUCUGCUGACAUUUAGUGGUGGAAGACCGAAAAUGUAAUAGCUCUGUGCUUGUGCGAGGGAGGACGGGCUUAUCAGCUGGAGCCUCAUGUAAAGGAACCUGGGGAGGCAUUUGUUGGGGCACAGCCCUCCCCUAGUUCUUGUUCCAUUGGGCUGCCUGCCCGCCCUCCCAUGCUGGAGGUUUCCGGUGCUGGAAGAUGCCAAGCCUUUGAGGAUGCAGAGUGUACCUUGGGUGGUUCUCCGCUUUGCCCGCUGCCGGGCUCCUGUGACGUUUGAUGACAUCACUGUGUACUUACUCCAGGAGGAAUGGGUGCUGCUGAGCCAGCAACAGAAGGAGCUCUGUGGUUCCAACAAGCUGGUGGCACCACUGGGACCAACUGUUGCCAAUCCUGAGCUGUUCCGCAAGUUCGGACGAGGGCCAGAGCCAUGGCUUGGCAGCGUCCAGGGCCAGAGGAGCCUUCUGGAGCAUCACCCAGGAAAAAAACAGAUGGGCUACAUGGGAGAAAUGGAGGUGCAAGGUCCCACCAGGGAGAGUGGACAGUCCCUCCCGCCUCAGAAGAAAGCCUACCUUUCCCACCUCAGUACAGGCAGUGGACACAUCGAGGGAGACUGGGCCGGAAGAAACAGGAAACUUCUGAAGCCCCGGUCCAUCCAGAAGUCGUGGUUUGUGCAGUUUCCGUGGCUGAUCAUGAAUGAGGAGCAGACGGCUCUGUUCUGCUCUGCUUGCCGAGAAUACCCCUCCAUCAGGGACAAACGGUCAAGACUAAUAGAAGGUUAUACAGGACCAUUCAAGGUGGAGACUCUCAAAUACCACGCGAAGAGCAAGGCCCACAUGUUCUGUGUCAAUGCCUUGGCAGCGAGGGACCCCAUCUGGGCAGCCCGGUUCCGGAGCAUCAGAGACCCACCUGGAGAUGUUCUGGCCAGCCCGGAGCCGCUCUUCACUGCAGAUUGCCCCAUAUUCUACCCCCCAGGGCCUCUGGGAGGAUUUGAUAGCAUGGCUGAGCUCCUGCCAAGUUCAAGAGCUGAACUAGAGGACCCUGGGGGGGAUGGAGCAAUUCCUGCAAUGUAUCUAGACUGCAUUUCAGAUUUGAGGCAAAAAGAAAUCACUGAUGGCAUCCACAGCUCCUCAGACAUUAAUAUUUUAUAUAAUGAUGCAGUAGAAUCCUGCAUUCAGGACCCUUCUGCAGAGGGGCUGUCGGAGGAGGUUCCUGUGGUGUUUGAGGAGCUGCCGGUGGUGUUCGAGGAUGUGGCAGUGUAUUUCACCCGGGAGGAGUGGGGCAUGCUAGACAAGCGGCAGAAGGAGCUGUACAGAGACGUGAUGCGGAUGAACUACGAGCUGUUGGCAUCCUUGGGACCUGCCGCUGCCAAGCCAGACUUGAUCUCCAAACUGGAGCGGAGGGCUGCACCCUGGAUCAAGGACCCAAAUGGGCCAAAGUGGGGGAAAGGUCGUCCUCCAGGGAACAAGAAGAUGGUGGCAGUGAGAGAGGCAGACACACAGGCCUCGGCUGCAGACUCCGCGUUGCUUCCAGGCUCUCCCGUGGAGGCCCGUGCCUCCUGCUGCAGUUCCAGCAUUUGUGAGGAAGGAGAUGGACCUAGGAGAAUCAAGAGGACAUACAGGCCCCGUUCCAUUCAGAGGUCAUGGUUUGGGCAGUUCCCAUGGUUAGUAAUUGACCCCAAAGAGACCAAACUCUUCUGCUCAGCCUGCAUAGAAAGACCUAAUCUCCAUGAUAAAUCAUCUCGGUUAGUCAGAGGUUACACGGGGCCUUUUAAAGUGGAGACUUUAAAAUACCAUGAAGUCAGCAAAGCGCACAGGCUCUGUGUCAACACGGUUGAAAUCAAGGAAGACACCCCUCACACUGCCCUCGUUCCAGAGAUCUCCAGCGACCUCAUGGCCAACAUGGAGCACUUUUUCAAUGCCGCCUACUCCAUUGCAUACCACUCAAGGCCCCUGAAUGACUUUGAGAAGAUCCUGCAGCUCCUCCAAAGCACGGGGACCGUGAUAUUAGGCAAGUACCGCAAUCGCACGGCGUGCACUCAGUUCAUCAAGUACAUCUCAGAGACCCUGAAGAGGGAGAUCCUGGAGGACGUGCGGAACUCGCCCUGUGUGAGCGUGCUGCUGGACAGCUCCACCGACGCCUCCGAGCAGGCCUGCGUGGGGAUUUACAUCCGCUACUUCAAGCAGAUGGAGGUGAAAGAGUCCUACAUCACUCUGGCCCCUCUCUACAGUGAGACAGCAGAUGGGUACUUCGAGACCAUCGUUUCUGCCCUGGAUGAGCUGGACAUCCCCUUCCGGAAGCCUGGCUGGGUGGUGGGGCUGGGGACGGAUGGCUCAGCCAUGUUGAGCUGCAGAGGAGGCCUUGUGGAAAAGUUCCAGGAGGUCAUCCCGCAGCUGCUGCCUGUCCACUGCGUGGCCCACCGGCUGCACCUGGCUGUGGUGGACGCCUGCGGGAGCAUCGAUCUGGUGAAGAAGUGUGACCGGCACAUCCGCACCGUCUUCAAGUUUUAUCAGUCCUCAAACAAGAGGCUGAACGAGCUGCAGGAAGGUGCGGCGCCUCUGGAGCAGGAGAUCAUCCGCCUGAAGGAUCUGAAUGCGGUCCGCUGGGUGGCCAGCAGGAGGCGCACGCUGCACGCGCUGCUCGUGAGCUGGCCCGCCCUGGCCAGGCACCUCCAGAGGGUGGCAGAGGCUGGGGGCCAGAUUGGGCACCGGGCCAAAGGGAUGCUGAAGCUCAUGCGCGGCUUCCACUUUGUCAAGUUCUGCCACUUCCUGUUGGACUUCCUGAGCAUCUACAGGCCUCUGUCCGAGGUGUGCCAGAAGGAGAUCGUGCUGAUUACAGAGGUGAACGCCACGCUGGGCCGCGCCUACGUGGCACUGGAGAGCCUCCGUCACCAGGCAGGGCCCAAAGAGGAAGAAUUCAACGCCAGCUUCAAGGAUGGGCGGCUCCACGGCAUCUGCUUGGACAAACUGGAGGUAGCGGAACAGCGGUUCCAGGCGGAUAGGGAGAGGACAGUCCUGACGGGGAUUGAGUACCUCCAGCAGAGGUUUGACGCAGACCGACCCCCACAGCUGAAGAACAUGGAGGUGUUUGACACCAUGGCCUGGCCAAGUGGGAUUGAACUUGCCAGUUUUGGGAAUGAUGACAUUCUCAACCUGGCCAGGUAUUUCGAGUGCUCCCUCCCAACAGGAUACAGUGAGGAAGCUCUGCUGGAGGAGUGGCUGGGCCUGAAAACCAUUGCCCAGCACCUCCCGUUCUCCAUGCUCUGCAAAAACGCCCUGGCCCAGCACUGCCGCUUCCCCCUGCUAAGCAAGCUCAUGGCCGUGGUGGUCUGUGUGCCCAUCUCCACCUCUUGCUGUGAGCGGGGGUUCAAGGCCAUGAACCGAAUCAGGACCGAUGAGAGGACCAAGCUCUCCAACGAGGUGCUCAACAUGCUCAUGAUGACAGCUGUGAACGGCGUGGCCGUCACGGAGUACGACCCCCAGCCCGCCAUCCAGCACUGGUACCUGACCUCCUCAGGCCGGCGUUUCAGCCAUGUCUACACCUGUGCCCAGGUGCCAGCCCGCUCCCCUGCAAGCGCCAGGCUCAGGAAGGAGGAGAUGGGAGCCCUCUAUGUGGAGGAGCCCAGGACCCAGAAGCCACCCAUCCUGCCCUCCAGGGAAGCAGCGGAGGUUCUGAAGGACUGCAUCAUGGAGCCUCCCGAGAGACUCCUGUAUCCCCACACCAGCCAGGAGGCCCCCGGGAUGUCCUGAGGGACAGGGAGUCCUUGGGACUGCCUUGGAGACGCCUCUGUGAUCACUGGGACAGGCUCUGCAGAUUCUAGGCUGCCCUAGGAUCUUCUGCUGGUGGCGAUGGUCUCUAAGCACCAGGAAGUGGGCAGUGGCAUCCCAGAGCAGCAGGGGUAUCAGGAGGUGCAUGACCUGUUUCCUGAGGCCCCACUCAGCACAGCCAUGCCUCACAGCACACAAAUGUGCCAGAAGGUUCUAUAUCUCAAGUUCAUUUUUAAGGUGCUGCAGAAAAUAACCCCAUCAUGAAAGGUUUCAGCCCCUGAGUUUUGGUGGCAAGAGGAGUGUCCUGGUAGGGGAGACUGUUGGACAUCCCUGGGGAAUGUUCCAGGGAGGCUGCCCACAGUCUAAGUGGGAAUGGGAAAGACCACCUUGUUAGAGGGGGAGGUUGCCCCUGCUCUAGGGACAGCUGGCCUGGCUGCAAGAGCCCCCAGAGGCAUUGUUCUGGGACUUCCUACCCUGGCUCCCACAGCAGAAGCAGUGAGGCCGUGGUCUCGUGCGGAACUCUACCUCUUCCCAGGGCUUCCUUUAGGGCGAAACAAUCACAAGCCCUUUGCACAGAGCACCCAAGAAAGUUCUCUUCCUGCAGCUCCAGAUGGUGGAGCUGGGCUCUUCUGGCAGGGGGUCUGGUGCUUCCCGGAGAGCCGAGCCGCGUUUAACCCGUGGCAUGCCCGGCCCGGUUUACCCAGGAGAGGAUGGGACGAAGUUGGAGUUGGGAGGCUUGGGAUGCAGCCCCAGCUCUGCUGCAGGCAGUGGUCUGAUUAAUCCCUUCCUCUUUGUGCCUCAGUUUCCCUCUCCAUGAAGUGGCAGCAGAGAUCCAAGUGCCUGCUGACUCCCCAUCUGCCCUAGGAUUAGUGAAUGAGAGCCUCGAGCUCCCUCAAAGACCUCUGGCUGCAGUGUGGACUUAGCUGCCAUCUGCCCCAUCCUCGUCCUUAGUGGGACAGGUAGGAAUUUGUCUCCAAAGUCCUUGUUGUAGGAGUUGCUCUCUGAAUGCACCAUCUGCACGACAGGCUAGUCCACUCUUCUCUGAGCUGCCCUGGGGACUCUGCACCAGGAUCUCCAGGGCCCACUGAGACAUCCCCGAAUGGGCGCUCAGUGACAAGGGCUUUGAACAACCUCCUCCAGGGACUUUGGGCCUGCUCUAGCUUCAGAACCACAGAACCACCGCCCUAGAGGCACAGAGGGGCUUCUGGCACUGCUAGGUUCACACCCUCCUCGCCCCGAUCUUCCUUCCACCUAAAGUGAAGCACUUUUCCUUCCAAGGGCAGCUCCGUCUUGGCAGGCUCAGGAGGCCGCUUAUCAGGAGGAGGAUGAUUUUGUCUAGGUUCUGCCUUCCUUAACCAUGGGCAGGAAAUGAGGCAAGUCAGCAGGCAGGGUUUCUCUGCCCUGCCUGAUACUUGUUUUAAACAGGCAGGAAGUGGGCGCCAUCCAUCCCAGCUUGCUUGCUGCCUGGCUCAGGCAGGUCCUGUGCUGUGCUGCAGGCCCCUGUGGGUGGGCCCUUUCUCCAUAGUCUGCCGCUUCCCAUUCCCAGGGUAGAUGCUGGCAUCUGAGCACCUGAGUACCCUUCCUAUUCCCAGGGUAGAAGCUGCUGUCUGAGUACCCUUCCCAUUCCCAGGGUAGAUGCUGGCAUCUGAGCACCUGAGUACCCUUCCUAUUCCCAGGGUAGAAGCUGCUGUCUGAGUACCCUUCCCAUUCCCAGGGUAGAUGCUGGCGUCCGAGCCCCUCCCUGGUACCGCAGGUACCCUGGUACCCCACCUGCCCUUUCAUCCCCACCCCAGUACUUAGCCUUAGCACUGUUGCUUUCGUGUCAUUUUCAGUUCUAGUCAGGAAUUCCUUUCUUGCUUUCUGCCUUUGACCUGUGGAAAUGUCUCCCAGCCCUGUGGGUCUGGCGGUCAGAGGGACCCCACAGGCCUGUGGUGCGGGAGCUCUGGGAGGUGUUACUAUCUGCGUGGCUAAGGCACACACAGGCCUCCUUCUCCCCAUCACCGUCUCCAUGGGCGUUCAGGAACUUGCCCAGGUCAGGCACUGUGGAUGUGAACUCGUGGAAAGGGAGGGAGAAAGGCUUUUUUAGGUGGGGCUAUAGCCUCUGCCCUACCCACAGGGAUUCCACAUCAAGGUGCUGUUCCAGCACACAUGCUUCCUGCGGCCUCUUCAUCCUUGAAGAAUCCCUCAGAGCAGGAGGCCAUCCUGUGAGCAGCCGUGAGUGGGUCUCUGUGGGAGUAGUUCUGGAGCUGAGGUGGAAGCUAGGGGAAGCAACUCGCCCUCUCCACGUCAGCAUCAGCGUGCUCCGAGGACACCGGCCAGUGCCUUCCUUAGGUGGUGGGAAAGGGGGGUCCCUGUGCAGCGGGGCCACUGAGAAUGCUGUUUGUCAUAAAAUUUGCACUACCCGAUUUCUCAAGGGGCACAGGCCUGCUCCGUUCCCCUUUGUCAGCCAAUGGCCAAGAAGGAAGAAGAUGACUGCCAUCUUAUUCCUGAACUUCCUCAUUCAGGACCCCCGUGGAAACACAGUGAGCAUCCUUAUCAGAGGCCCUGGCCCAGGCUGGCCCCUUUGCUUUGUUUGGAGAGGCUGGCUGAGUUUCAGCCCCUAGUGCUGGAGACCCCCUUGUUGGAGAGGCUUCCUGUUUAUGCCUCACAAGAAGAAAAACCACAGGGCUCUGGGAGGGGAAGAAGCAUGCACUCCCGCUUUGGCUGGAGUCCCAGCGCUUGUCGCCACCCUCCUCCUUGCCUGUAGUCUUGACAGCAUCCGUAUGUACGUGUCCUGGCAUUUCCCCUCCCUCUCCCUGAUGACUGAUACCCACCGGGUCUGACAUUCCAAGUAACCAGUAUGUAACUGGUAGUUUGAUCCCAAUAGCCAUAGCGACUCCAGGUGGGAGUGAGGGAGCCCAGCCCCCUGUCCUGGAAGAUACCUUAGAGUAUGUGACCGCGCUCCAGACCCUUGCUUCUCUCUCCUGCAGAGGAUGAGUUUCUAGGGUGCUAAGUACCUAUCAGAACAGUGUGGAGGGGCGGGUCCCUCAUACAGGUGUGUGCUUAGCCAAAUACAGUAACUGUGACUGGCCCAGGGAUGUUCUCUCCUCUAUUUUCAAAGAUGAAAGGAGGUUUUAAAAACCAUGUUUGAUUCCUAACCUUUUGCUACCUGAAUAAAGCAGAGUCUAUUUCAACACA